GUUCUGCUGGACUGAGCUGGUUGCCUCAUGUUAUUAUGCAGGCAACUCACUUUAUCCCAAUUUCUUGAUACUUUUCCUUCUGGAGGUCCUAUUUCUCUAACAUCUUCCAGAAAAGUCUUAAAGCUGCCUUAACCUUUUUUCCAGUCCACCUCUUAAAUUUUUUCCUCCUCUUCCUCUAUACUAACAUGAGUGUGGAUCCAGCUUGUCCCCAAAGCUUGCCUUGCUUUGAAGAAUCCGACUGUAAAGAAUCUUCACCUAUGCCUGUGAUUUGUGGGCCUGAAGAAAACUAUCCAUCCUUGCAAAUGUCUUCUGCUGAGAUGCCUCACACAGAGACUGUCUCUCCUCUUCCUUCCUCCAUGGAUCUGCUUAUUCAGGACAGCCCUGAUUCUUCCACCAGUCCCAAAGGCAAACAACCCACUUCUGCAGAGAAUAGUGUCGCAAAAAAGGAAGACAAGGUCCCGGUCAAGAAACAGAAGACCAGAACUGUGUUCUCUUCCACCCAGCUGUGUGUACUCAAUGAUAGAUUUCAGAGACAGAAAUACCUCAGCCUCCAGCAGAUGCAAGAACUCUCCAACAUCCUGAACCUCAGCUACAAACAGGUGAAGACCUGGUUCCAGAACCAGAGAAUGAAAUCUAAGAGGUGGCAGAAAAACAACUGGCCGAAGAAUAGCAAUGGUGUGACGCAGAAGGCCUCAGCACCUACCUACCCCAGCCUCUACUCUUCCUACCACCAGGGAUGCCUGGUGAACCCGACUGGGAACCUUCCAAUGUGGAGCAACCAGACCUGGAACAAUUCAACCUGGAGCAACCAGACCCAGAACAUCCAGUCCUGGAGCAACCACUCCUGGAACACUCAGACCUGGUGCACCCAAUCCUGGAACAAUCAGGCCUGGAACAGUCCCUUCUAUAACUGUGGAGAGGAAUCUCUGCAGUCCUGCAUGCACUUCCAGCCAAAUUCUCCUGCCAGUGACUUGGAGGCUGCCUUGGAAGCUGCUGGGGAAGGCCUUAAUGUAAUACAGCAGACCACUAGGUAUUUUAGUACUCCACAAACCAUGGAUUUAUUCCUAAACUACUCCAUGAACAUGCAACCUGAAGACGUGUGAAGAUGAGUGAAACUGAUAUUACUCAAUUUCAGUCUGGACACUGGCUGAAUCCUUCCUCUCCCCUCCUCCCAUCCUUCAUAGGAUUUUUCUUGUUUGGAAACCACGUGUUCUGGUUUCCAUGAUGCCCAUCCAGUCAAUCUCAUGGAGGGUGGAGUAUGGUUGGAGCCUAAUCAGCGAGGUUUCUUUUUUUUUUUUUUUUUCCUAUUGGAUCUUCCUGGAGAAAAUACUUUUUUUUUUUUUUUUUUUUGAGACGGAGUCUUGCUCUGUCGCCCAGGCUGGAGUGCAGUGGCGCGGUCUUGGCUCACUGCAAGCUCCGUCUGCCGGGUUCACGCCAUUCUCCUGCCUCAGCCUCCCGAGCAGCUGGGACUACAGGCGCCCGCCACCUCGCCCGGCUAAUAUUUUGUAUUUUUAGUAGAGACGGGGUUUCACUGUGUUAGCCAGGAUGGUCUCGAUCUCCUGACCUUGUGAUCCGCCCGCCUCGGCCUCCCUAACAGCUGGGAUUUACAGGCGUGAGCCACCGCGCCCUGCCUAGAAAAGACAUUUUAAUAACCUUGGCUGCCGUCUCUGGCUAUAGAUAAGUAGAUCUAAUACGAGUUUGGAUAUCUUUAGGGUUUAGAAUCUAACCUCAAGAAUAAGAAAUACAAGUACAAAUUGGUGAUGAAGAUGUAUUCGUAUUGUUUGGGAUUGGGAGGCUUUGCUUAUUUUUUAAAAACUAUUGAGGUAAAGGGUUAAGCUGUAACAUACUUAAUUGAUUUCUUACCGUUUUUGGCUCUGUUUUGCUAU